ACUUCAGUGGAUCCCGCGCCGGGGCCGCGGGCGGAGCUGCCUGCCGGUCCCGCGCCGCGCGUCCGCACUCCUCGGCCCUCGGGCGGUCGAUGGGACGGGGCGCCGCGGAGCAGGAGGCGGCGCCCGUCGGGGUGCUCGGGCCGCGCGGGAGCCCACUGUGGGGCUCGGGCAUGGCGGGCCGCAGGACCUGAGCUCUCCUCAGGGGAGCGGGGAGGCAGCUGCUGGCCGGCGAUGGGGACGGAGUGGGGCCGUCGCCGCCGCGCCGAGCCGUGAGCGCCGAGCCACCGCCGCCGCUACCUCAGCCCUUCGCGAAGCGCCGGGCAGCUCGGGAACAUGGCCCUGGAGCGGCUCUGCUCGGUCCUCAAAGUGUUGUUAAUAACAGUACUGGUAGUGGAAGGGAUUGCCGUGGCCCAAAAAACCCAAGAUGGACAAAAUAUUGGAAUCAAGCAUAUUCCUGCAACCCAGUGUGGCAUUUGGGUUCGAACCAGCAAUGGAGGUCAUUUUGCUUCGCCAAAUUAUCCUGACUCAUAUCCACCAAACAAGGAGUGUAUCUACAUUUUGGAAGCUGCUCCACGUCAAAGAAUAGAGUUGACCUUUGAUGAACAUUAUUAUAUAGAACCAUCAUUUGAGUGUCGGUUUGAUCACUUGGAAGUUCGAGAUGGGCCAUUUGGUUUCUCUCCUCUUAUAGAUCGUUACUGUGGCGUGAAAAGCCCUCCAUUAAUUAGAUCAACAGGGAGAUUCAUGUGGAUUAAGUUUAGUUCUGAUGAAGAGCUUGAAGGACUGGGAUUUCGAGCAAAAUAUUCAUUUAUUCCAGAUCCAGACUUUACUUACCUAGGAGGUAUUUUAAAUCCCAUUCCAGAUUGUCAGUUCGAGCUCUCGGGAGCUGAUGGAAUAGUGCGCUCUAGUCAGGUAGAACAAGAGGAGAAAACAAAACCAGGCCAAGCCGUUGAUUGCAUCUGGACCAUUAAAGCCACUCCAAAAGCUAAGAUUUAUUUGAGGUUCCUAGAUUAUCAAAUGGAGCACUCAAAUGAAUGCAAGAGAAACUUCGUUGCAGUCUAUGAUGGAAGCAGUUCUAUUGAAAACCUGAAGGCCAAGUUUUGCAGCACUGUGGCCAAUGAUGUAAUGCUUAAAACAGGAAUUGGAGUGAUUCGAAUGUGGGCAGAUGAAGGUAGUCGGCUUAGCAGGUUUCGAAUGCUCUUUACUUCCUUUGUGGAGCCUCCCUGCACAAGCAGCACUUUCUUUUGCCAUAGCAACAUGUGCAUCAAUAAUUCUUUAGUCUGUAAUGGUGUCCAAAAUUGUGCAUACCCUUGGGAUGAAAAUCAUUGUAAAGAAAAGAAAAAAGCAGGAGUAUUUGAACAAAUCACUAAGACUCAUGGAACAAUUAUUGGCAUUACUUCAGGGAUUGUCUUGGUCCUUCUCAUUAUUUCUAUUUUAGUACAAGUGAAACAGCCUCGAAAAAAGGUCAUGGCUUGCAAAACCGCUUUUAAUAAAACCGGGUUCCAAGAAGUGUUUGAUCCUCCUCAUUAUGAACUGUUUUCACUAAGGGACAAAGAGAUUUCUGCAGACCUGGCAGACUUGUCGGAAGAAUUGGACAACUACCAGAAGAUGCGGCGCUCCUCCACCGCCUCCCGCUGCAUCCACGACCACCACUGUGGGUCGCAGGCCUCCAGCGUCAAACAAAGCAGGACCAACCUCAGUUCCAUGGAACUUCCUUUCCGAAAUGACUUUGCACAACCACAGCCAAUGAAAACAUUUAAUAGCACCUUCAAGAAAAGUAGUUACACUUUCAAACAGGGACAUGAGUGCCCUGAGCAGGCCCUGGAAGACCGAGUAAUGGAGGAGAUUCCCUGUGAAAUUUAUGUCAGGGGGCGAGAAGAUUCUGCACAAGCAUCCAUAUCCAUUGACUUCUAAUCUUCUGCUAAUGGUGAUGUGAAUUCUUAGGGUGUGUACGUACGCAGCCUCCAGGGCACCAUACUGUUUCCAGCAGCCAACCCUUUUCUCCCAUCACAACUACGAAGACCUUGAUUUACCGUUAACCUAUUGUAUGGUGAUGUUUUUAUUCUCUCAGGCAGUCUAUAUAUGUUAAACCAAUCAAGGAACUUACUCUAUUCAGUGGAAACAAUAAUCAUCUCUAUUGCUUGGUGUCAUUUAUAGGAAGCACUGCCAGUUAAAGAGCAUUAGAAGAGGUGGUUGGAUGGAGCCAGGCUCAGGCUGCCUCUUCGUUUUAGCAACAAGAAGACUGCUCUUGACUGAUAACAGCUCUGUCAAUAUUUUGAUGCCACAAUAAACUUGAUUUUUCUUUACAUUCCUUUUAUUUUUCCUUUCUCUAAAUUUAAUUUGUUUUAUAAGCCUAUCGUUUUACCAUUUCAUUUUCUUACAUAAGUACAAGUGGUUAAUGUACCACAUACUUCAGUAUAGGCAUUUGUUCUUGAGUGUGUCAAAAUACAGCUAGUUACUGUGCCAAUUAAGACCCAGUUGUAUUUCACCCAUCUGUUUCUUCUUGGCUAAUCUCUGUACUUCUGCCUUUUAAUUACUGGGCCCUUAUUCCUUAUUUUCUGUGAGAAAUAAUAGAUGAUAUGAUUUAUUACCUUUCAAUUAUAUUUUUCUCAGUUAUACUAGAAAAUUUCAUAAUCCUGGGAUAUAUGUACCAUUGUCAGCUAUGACUAAAAAUUUGAAAAAGAUAAAAAUUUCUAGCAAGCCUUUGAAGUUUACCAAGUAUAGUCACAUUCAGUGACAGCCCAUUCAUUCCAGUAAAGAAUCAUUUCAUUCACUUUGGGAGAGGCCUAUAAUUACAUUUAUUUGCAAUGUUUCUCUUCGCUAGAUUGUUACAUAGCUCCCAUUCUGUUGGUUUUGCUUACAGCAUAUGGUAACCAAGGUUAGAUGCCAGUUAAAAUUCCUUAGAAAUUGGAUGAGCCUUGAGAUUGCUUCUUAACUGGGACAUGACAUUUUUCUAGCUCUUAUCAAGAAUAACAACUUCCACUUUUUUUUAAACUGCACUUUUGACUUUUUUUAUGGUAUAAAAACAAUAAUUUAUAAACAUAAAAGCUCAUUGUGUUUUUUAGACUUUUGAUAUUAUUUGAUACUGUACAAACUUUAUUAAAUCAAGAUGAAAGACCUACAGGACAGAUUCCUUUCAGUGUUCACAUCAGUGGCUUUGUAUGCAAAUAUGCUGUGUUGGACCUGGACGCUAUAACUUAUUGUAAAGACCUUGGAAAUGUGGACAUAAGCUCUUUCUUUCCUUUUGUUACUGUAUUUAGUUUGUGAUAAAUUUUUCACUGUGUGAUAUUUAUGCUCUAAAUCACUACACAAAUCCCAUAUUAAAAUAUACAUUGUACCUGACCCUUUAAUCAUGUUAUUUAUGCCACCAAGGUUGUGGAUCUUAAGGUAUGUAUGGAAAGGAACUCAUUUAUCAAAUUGUAAGUAAUACAGACAUGCCAUUUAAAAGAGGUAAAUUCUUGUUUUCUAUAUUUUGUUAGUAAAUUCUCAAUGAAAUAAGUUGAAGUUUCACUGGAUUUCAUUAACUUUUAAAUAUUACAUAUAUGUGUUUUCUCAGAUUAGUGAAAAUUGUGACCUUAAAUUUAAUACACAUAUACUGCCUCAGAGUGCUUUCUUGUAUCAAAAUUUUUGUUUUUUAAAAAAGUAGAUAAUAUUUAGGAGACAGAAAAACCUAUACAUAAUGUAUUCAUGAUUUAAAUUUUUUUAAGUCAGCCUAGUUUCUUGUUUUAAAAAUAUAACGUGGAAACAUGAAAAGACUUGAUGCAUAUAAUAUUCAAUGAACUAAUACCAGAGACAGCUAAGUUUUUUCAGUAGUUAUGCUGAAUAAGCAUUUUAGUAGGUAACUUACACCAGCUAACAUUUGAACAGCAUAAUAAAUACUUAAUAUAACAACAACUAUGAUCUUAUGAUGAUAAAAGGGAAGUUAGCAUAUUUUCUAUGUAAAAUUAUUCAUUUUUUAAAAUAGCUGUUAAACCUAUAUUUAAUCUUUAGAUUAUAAUAGCAAAUAAUACAGUAUGCUAAACUAUAGUCACUUGUAACUACAUUUUUGUUUUUGAAAUUUGAUUUCUAUUUAUAAGGUCUUGAAGAGGCCUACAAAAUACAGAGCCUUUAAAGAAGACAUAACAGUAAAAUAGAAGUACACAGUUUUAUACGAGUCAAUGUAGCAAGUAACAUUUAGACAGUAAGUUUGGUUCUGAAUUUUCUGGCUGCUAAAACACUUUUUGCUUUUCACAGUAAAAAAACUUAUGUGCAGAGGCUAAUUUCCUCUUGAACUACAGCAUGAGGGUCUGUAUAUAGGAACAUUUCUUCAGAAUGUAAAAAAGAUGCAAAAUGGAGACAGAGGUUAUAAUGGUGCUUCUUAACCCAGUGAAGGCACAACUUAAUGUCGUCUAGGAACAUUGGUUUAGGGUCAGUCUGUAUUUUCAGGGAUAGAACUAAAGAACCAGAUGAUCAAUAGCUAAGCCAGCCUUAGCCUGUCACAUGUUAUACACCUUCAUUGAAUCAUAGAUGGGCAUUAGAUCUCAUUUAUUUAUUAAACUUCUCUAUGCUUUUGGAAGAGGUAAGAAUGGAACUAAUAAAUCUUAGGCAUUAUUGCCAGAAUAAUGCUAAUUGCUGUAUAUACAGCCUUUAAUCUUUGAGAUCAGUGAGAAAACUUUAUAAAUUGCUUACUAAAAUGAAAGCCAUAAAAUUUAAUAACAGAAGACAUGAAAUUUAGCAAUCUUGUGGAAUUCAUUACACAGUAUUAACUGUCACGCAGGGUACCCCACACAGUGUCCCAGUGUUGAACACAAAAUGCAAAUCUGGAAGGGAUAAAUAUCUUCAAUUCAGAAACAGCAUUAAGUAUACCUGUAUAAUACUGUCACCAUUAUCUUCCAUCUGCAAUUCACCGCAUCAUCCCCCAAAUGCCCACAGAUCUAUUGCAGGAAACCUACUAAUCCCAACAUCUAAAGCAUGUAGGAAUAAGAUGUGAUAUUCCUUUUGUGUGUGGGGAGAGUGUCAAUCUAAACGUUUAACAAAAGGCAAAGAAUGUUCACAUUUCACAUCACAAAAGAGAUUUCAAAGACUCCUUUAACCCGACAGCGCUUAUGUCAGUGUCUUUGUCAUGUUUCAUAGAAUUGUUAGACUUUAAAAGAACCUCCUGAAAGUCUGCCUCUGAACAUUUGUAUGGUUCUGCCAAUGUCUGAUGAGAAGAAUGCUUCCCUGUUUGAGGAGUGUGUUCACUGAUGAGAGGGGACGGGAGAAGCCUGGUUGUGAUUUCAGGAAUAAUUCUCAAAGGAGAUUAUACUCUUAUUGCAAAAUGGGGUCUGCUAUAUAUUGUUCAUGUCACUUUAUUGCAAGUGACAUGAAUUAUAUGACAUUAAAAAUAAUAUGCCUUGAAUCACACUGAUUAGACCCAGAAGGAUCAUUGAGUUUUUGGUGGUUUUAAAGAUCCAAGAAAGACCUAUCUAGCCCAAGUGUAUGAAUGAGAAGACUGAAGCCCACAGAAGUGAACUCAGCACCAGUGUCUCAAGAACCCCAGUACUCUGGUUUUUUUCUUUUUUGAGACGGAGUCUCGCUCUGUCGCCCAGGCUGGAGUGCAGUGGCGCGAUCUCGGCUCACUGCAAGCUCCGCCUCCCGGGUUCACGCUAUUCUCCUGCCUCAGUCUCCCAAGUAGCUGGGACUACAGGCGCCCGACACCAUGCCCGGCUAAUUUCUUGUAUUUUUAGUAGAGACGGGGUUUCACCGUGUUAGCCAGGAUAGUCUCAAUCUCCUGACCUCGUGAUCCACCCGCCUCGGCCUCCCAAAGUGCUGGGAUUACAGGCGUGAGCCACCGCGCCUGGCCUUCUGUUUUUGUUUUUCUGUUUUUUUGUUUUUUGAGACAGAGUCUCGCUCUGUCACCCAGGCUAGAGUGCAGUGGCGUGAUCUCGGCUCACUGCAAGCUCCGCCUCCCGGGUUCAUGCCAUUCUCCUGUCUCAGCCUCUCGAGUAGCUGGGACUACAGGCGCCCGCCACCAUGCCCGGCUAAUUUUUUGUAUUUUUAGUAGAGACGGGGUUUCACCAUGUUAGCCAGGAUGGUCUCGAUCUCCUGACCUCGUGAUCCGCCCGCCUCGGCCUCCCAAAGUGCUGGGAUUACAGGAGUGAGCCAAGGCGCCCAGCCCAGCUGUACGUUUUAAAAGUCAAGCACUUCUGUUUAGCAGCCCAUGUAAGCUUGUCAAUCAUUCUGAAUUGAAAUGUAAUUUAUUCUGUAAUUUCUUCAAUGCAUUAUAUUUCCCCUUUUCUUUAAAUGUAUGUAACAUUGUGUUCUACAGUUUUGCUGCCAUGAUUCCUUGGCACCGUGAAUUCUUACUAAGCAAUGUUUGUUAACAGUAUACAGGCUCGAUACUAGGCAGGAAGAGCUCCUGUGUUCUUGCUUUUUUGAUCUUUUUUAAAUCUAAAGGAGACGUGUAUUCUAGAAAUUAAAUAUUUGUGUGCCAUAUCUCUUGAGUUUUGGAGAAUGAUUGGAGUUUGAGUUACUGUAAAUAACAAGAUUAUCUUGGAUAUUUUAGUUUUCUGCAAAAUCACUUAUGUUUUAUAUACCUCUGCUAAUAAUUCAAAACUCUGAAUUUGCUUUACUUUAACUUUUUAAAAAUGUAUUUUUGCAAUUGGUUUAAUGACUACCAAAGCCUAAAAAGCUAAUGACUAGGGUGCAUGUUUAGUAUGCACUGUCUAGUGUAAGCUUUUUAAAAGCAGUAGAUUUUUAUUAGAGAUGAACUUCCAGGCCAUAUGAGAAUAUGCUUAAUCCUAGAUUUGGCAUUUUAUAGAAAAGAAUUUUGACUCUUGAACUAGAAUUAAAAACUUGUUCUGAUUUCCUUGCUUGCCUCAAUUUCUAAAGUCUAGAAGUGGCAAAUAAUUUAGAUCACUUAUACCAACAGAAUCUGUAUUUCCUUCCGGGGCAAAGUUGGCAUUUCCUAUCCACUAGCUUCCAAAAUACAAUAAUCCUAGUUAUGAUAAGGGCAACUUUAUUUUAUUACACUUAGAACCAUUUUAUGUUUUCAAAUUCAUUAAUCUUCAAGUGAAGAUGAACUAAAGAAAAAAAUGCGUUUUGUCCCAGGUUGCCUGCAGGUUGCAGUCUGCUGCAUCCGGUCACUGAAGAGGCAGUGAGGACUGUCACAGAGUGGGCUGGAGAGCCAAGCUGUUCUUUCGGGGUGCACAGUGCACCAGCCAUAACACAGCUUAGAAACAUGGAUGAGUAUACCUCAAGACAGGUGAACACGGAGUGGGGAGCAAAAGAAGGCAGAAACUCCUCUGAGUUUCACAAGCAUCAGGCACAGAUCAGGGCACAGAGGAAGAAGAAAGAAGGUUUACCACUGGUCUGUCUCUGUAAAUUGUUACAGAGCAAUUUUACUUUGUGUUAUUUAGGAUCAAGAAACAAGUGUUAUUUAAAAGUUCUCUUACCCUCCAACCUUUGUCAUACU